CAGAGAAGCGGCUGCUAGAGAUGGGCCUGAGGCGGGCUCAGGGCCCCGAUGGGGGCCUGACAGCCUCCACCUACAGCUACCUGGGCGAUGUUGGCGCCAGCAGCUGGUGAGGGCCCUGGGGUGGACCUGGCGGCCAAAGCCCAGGUGUGGCUGGAGCAGGUGUGUGCCCACCUGGGGCUGGGGGUGCAGGAGCCGCAUCCAGGCGAGCGGGCAGCCUUUGUGGCCUAUGCCUUGGCUUUUCCCCGGGCCUUCCAGGGCCUCCUGGACACCUACAGCGUGUGGAGGAGUGGUCUCCCCAACUUCCUAGCAGUCGCCCUGGCCCUGGGAGAGCUGGGCUACCGGGCAGUGGGCGUGAGGCUGGACAGUGGUGACCUGCUACAGCAGGCUCAGGAGAUCCGCAAGGUCUUCCGAGCUGCUGCAGCCCAGUUCCAGGUGCCCUGGCUGGAGUCAGUCCUCAUCGUAGUCAGCAACAACAUUGACGAGGAGGCGCUGGCCCGACUGGCCCAGGAGGGCAGUGAGGUGAAUGUCAUUGGCAUUGGCACCAGUGUGGUCACCUGCCCCCAACAGCCUUCCCUGGGUGGCGUCUAUAAGCUGGUGGCCGUGGGGGGCCAGCCACGAAUGAAGCUGACCGAGGACCCCGAGAAGCAGACGUUGCCUGGGAGCAAGGCUGCUUUCCGGCUCCUGGGCUCUGACGGGUCUCCACUCAUGGACAUGCUGCAGUUAGCAGAAGAGCCAGUGCCACAGGCUGGGCAGGAGCUGAGGGUGUGGCCUCCAGGGGCCCAGGAGCCCUGCACCGUGAGGCCAGCCCAGGUGGAGCCACUACUGCGGCUCUGCCUCCAGCAGGGACAGCUGUGUGAGCCGCUCCCAUCCCUGGCAGAGUCUAGAGCCUUGGCCCAGCUGUCCCUGAGCCGACUCAGCCCUGAGCACAGGCGGCUGCGGAGCCCUGCACAGUACCAGGUUGGGGGGAGGCCCACCCUGUCAUUCUGCCCUGUGCGCCCCCGCCCUCACCCUGCCCACCGCUCCUGUCCUCUGCUCCCUGCAGGUGGUGCUGUCCGAGAGGCUGCAGGCCCUGGUGAACAGUCUGUGUGCGGGGCAGUCCCCCUGAGACUCGGAGCGGGGCUGACUGGAAACAACACGAAUCACUCACUUUUCCCCACAGCUUGUCCUGUGUUGUUUGUGUCGUUUGUUCACCCAGCCCACGGGCUGCGCCUCCCGGGCUGCGGCUGGGCUGGAGUCGGGAAUCUGAGCUCGAGGUAGCAGGAAGAUUUGCAUCCCAGUGAAAGCACAGGCCCUGCCGGCGUGGGAGACAGCCCUGUGCUGAAGCCCGAAGGGCAGUGAGGAGUUCCCCGGCUUUGGGUAGGCUGUGGGGAGUCAGAUCCCACACUAGAACUACAAAGCCACAGGCAGGGAGGGCUUUGGUGUCUGCCUUGGAGUUGAGGGAGUUGCUGCAGACCUUUCCUUGCUAGAGGCAGGCUGGGGACAGGACAGGGUUGGGGGUAGUGCCAGGUAAGAGGGUCCAGCCGUGGCCCUGGGCUCCCACGCCUGCCUAGGCACUGCCCCCCAGGCUCAGGGUCAGUGAAGACGUCUCAAACUCCCCAAGUCAAAAGGGAGUGCUCAGGUGUCUCCUGCCACUGCUGCUGCCAACCCAGCACCACCCUGGCAUCUGGCGUCAGGGACACAGCUCCUGACCCAGCAGCCCACGGAAGGAGAGGAAGAAUGGGGAAGAAGUUGAAGCUCCAGGAGAUGACUCAGCCCCAGACACCUGGCCAGAGUGGCACUGCACGUGGCUGUGCUGGGCUGGCCCUGCCUCUGCACCAGCAAGUUCCUGAUCUCAGGGUUCCGCCAGUUUGGGCAACGUGAGCUUCAAGAGGAACUGCUUGGGGGAGAGGUUCUAGGCUUGGCAGGAAGUGGAGGCUGGGGGCCUGGGCCUCUCUUGUCGAAGCAGCCUGAGGUGGCACAGACAGGCAAGGGUGUGGGGGGAAUGCUGACCGCCUGGGGCACUUCCGUCUGCCCAGGCAUUCCACCAGACCAGCUCACCUGGCUCCCCGGGCUUCAGGGUGGGCAGCACCACUGUGUGGUUGGCUGAGGGUGGAGGGUGGGGACUUGGAGCAGAGGCCCAGUCCAGCCAGCCCCGGGGAGUACGAGCUAGGAGAGAGAUACAGACUCACACACAUUGGACAGAACACACCACACCCCAGGCACCCCCAGGGCACCCGCGCACUCCGAGGGGCCCAGCCAGAGUGGCUGUAUUCUUCCGUUCUUGCACUGCUGUAAAGAAAUACCUGAGACUGGGUAAUUUCUAAGGAAGAGAGGUUUAAUUGGCCUGUGGUUCUGCAGGUACAGGAAGCAUGGCUGGGGAGGCUUCAGGAAACUUACCAUCUUGGUGGAAGCGGAAGCGGGCAGGUCUUACAUGGCCGGAGGAAGGGGUGGGGCGGUGCCACGCACUUCCAGACAACCAGAUCUUGAGAAGUCUUAUCAUGGGAACAGCACCAAAGGGGGAAGUUGCCCCCAGGAUCCAAUCACUUCCCACCAGGCCCCACCUCCAGCACUGGGGAUUACGUUUCAACAUGAGAUUUGGCCAAGGACCCAGGACCCAGAGGGGCCUGCACAAGCUCUGGAGGGGCCACCGCUCCUCUGGUGUCUUCACUGCCCCCUCCACACCUCCGGGCUGCCCCAAGCUCACCCAGUCAUGCCUGUUGCAAGGUGUCUGACAGAGCCAGCGUGCAGGGGGCGGAGCCAGCGUGCAGGGGGCGGGGCCAGCCCCUAGCCCCAGGCCCAGUGGGGAGCUGACUGCUGCUUGGGGGCUGAAUCAGGCCUCGACUCAGGGUGGGGCCCAGACUCCUGGACCCUGCGAGGACCUCCUCAGAGCUGUCCACAACUGCCCUGAGCUCCCUGGUCAACAGGGGCUGGUAGUCAGGGUGGGGGCCCUUCUCCCCCUUUCUUCGUGGAUCUGCCAGCUCUUGGGGAUCCUGUUCUCAGGGCCCUGGUGGGUAGAGCCACACCACAGGCACUCAGGCUGCAGGUGGCCACUCCCCUCCAGCAGCCCAGGCAGGAGGGCCCCUCAAAGGC